CUCUGGCUCCCAGCCCCGCAGCGGCCGAGCUGCAGCCCGGGCUCAGUCUCCGCCGCCGCCGUGAACAUGGAGCCCCCGGACGCACCGGCCCAGGCGCGCGGGGCCCCGCGGCUGCUGUUGCUCGCAGUCCUGCUGGCGGCGCACCCAGAUGCCCAGGCGGAGGUGCGCUUGUCUGUACCCCCGCUGGUGGAGGUGAUGCGAGGAAAGUCUGUCAUUCUGGACUGCACCCCUACGGGAACCCACGACCAUUAUAUGCUGGAAUGGUUCCUUACCGACCGCUCGGGAGCUCGCCCCCGCCUAGCCUCGGCUGAGAUGCAGGGCUCUGAGCUCCAGGUCACAAUGCACGACACCCGGGGCCGCAGUCCCCCAUACCAGCUGGACUCCCAGGGGCGCCUGGUGCUGGCUGAGGCCCAGGUGGGCGACGAGCGAGACUACGUGUGCGUGGUGAGGGCAGGGGCGGCAGGCACUGCUGAGGCCACUGCGCGGCUCAACGUGUUUGCAAAGCCAGAGGCCACUGAGGUCUCCCCCAACAAAGGGACACUGUCUGUGAUGGAGGACUCUGCCCAGGAGAUCGCCACCUGCAACAGCCGGAACGGGAACCCGGCCCCCAAGAUCACGUGGUAUCGCAACGGGCAGCGCCUGGAGGUGCCCGUAGAGAUGAACCCAGAGGGCUACAUGACCAGCCGCACGGUCCGGGAGGCCUCGGGCCUGCUCUCCCUCACCAGCACCCUCUACCUGCGGCUCCGCAAGGAUGACCGAGACGCCAGCUUCCACUGCGCCGCCCACUACAGCCUGCCCGAGGGCCGCCACGGCCGCCUGGACAGCCCCACCUUCCACCUCACCCUGCACUAUCCCACGGAGCACGUGCAGUUCUGGGUGGGCAGCCCGUCCACCCCAGCAGGCUGGGUACGCGAGGGUGACACUGUCCAGCUGCUCUGCCGGGGGGACGGCAGCCCCAGCCCGGAGUAUACGCUUUUCCGCCUUCAGGAUGAGCAGGAGGAAGUGCUGAAUGUGAAUCUCGAGGGGAACUUGACCCUGGAGGGAGUGACCCGGGGCCAGAGCGGGACCUAUGGCUGCAGAGUGGAGGAUUACGACGCGGCAGAUGACGUGCAGCUCUCCAAGACGCUGGAGCUGCGCGUGGCCUAUCUGGACCCCCUGGAGCUCAGCGAGGGGAAGGUGCUUUCCUUACCUCUAAACAGCAGUGCAGUCGUGAACUGCUCCGUGCACGGCCUGCCCACCCCUGCCCUACGCUGGACCAAGGACUCCACUCCCCUGGGCGAUGGCCCCAUGCUGUCGCUCAGUUCUAUCACCUUCGAUUCCAAUGGCACCUACGUAUGUGAGGCCUCCCUGCCCACAGUCCCGGUCCUCAGCCGCACCCAGAACUUCACGCUGCUGGUCCAAGGCUCGCCAGAGCUAAAGACAGCGGAAAUAGAGCCCAAGGCAGAUGGCAGCUGGAGGGAAGGAGACGAAGUCACACUCAUCUGCUCUGCCCGCGGCCAUCCAGACCCCAAACUCAGCUGGAGCCAAUUGGGGGGCAGCCCCGCAGAGCCAAUCCCCGGACGGCAGGGUUGGGUGAGCAGCUCUCUGACCCUGAAAGUGACCAGCGCCCUGAGCCGCGAUGGCAUCUCCUGUGAAGCCUCCAACCCCCACGGGAACAAGCGCCAUGUCUUCCACUUCGGCACCGUGAGCCCCCAGACCUCCCAGGCUGGAGUGGCCGUCAUGGCCGUGGCCGUCAGCGUGGGCCUCCUGCUCCUCGUCGUUGCUGUCUUCUACUGCGUGAGACGCAAAGGGGGCCCCUGCUGCCGCCAGCGGCGGGAGAAGGGGGCUCCGUGAGUGGCCUGCUAUCUGCAAUGACCACCAUAGCUUAACCCCAUCCCCACCCUCAACCCCAAGCUCAACCCAUAACCUCAACCACAUCUUAUCCUCCACCCCACAUCCCACCACAUCCACCUCCAUCCCCAACCCAUCCUCAUCCCCAACUACAGCCCCAAACCCAGCCCCAGACUAAUCCACAGCCAUCCCCAACUCAUCCUCAUCCCCAACUGCAGCCCCAAACCCAACCCAGGGCCAUCCCCAAACCCAUCCCCAAGCCAAACUCAACACCAUCCCCUUCCCUAAUCACCUCUCCUGCCCCUAGCUCAGCCUCAUCCCCAACUCCAUGCCUGUCUCCAAUCCCAACCCUGCCCCCAAUCUCCCCUCAACUCCAAUCCAUAACCCCCUUCAAACCAUCCUCAACUAAGCUCCUCUCCAGCCCUGGCCACAUCCCCAUCCUCCCCCAACCUCCAGCCCCAACACCCAUCAUCCCCCUGAGCUCACCCUUAACUCCAAUUUAUCCUCCAAGCCUAUCUCUCACCAUCCAGCCCUCACCUAGCCAUUUCCCAACCCUAGUCCUCCACCGUCCCGAAGCCAACUUCACCCAUGUCCCCAUCCCCAAUCUUGUCCCCAUUCCUGACUCCAAAUCCAACCCCUAAGCCUCCCCAAGCUCCUCCUCAUCUAACCUUGUCUCCAGCCCCAACCACAUGGCCGUCCUCACCUCCAAUCCGUAACCAUCCCAGACCGAUCCCAAAGCCAACUCCAGCUACAUUCCCACCUCCAACCCCAAUAGCAUCUGCAUCCCCAUGCCCAACCCUAACCCCAGUGCCAUUACCAGCCCCUACCCCAUCCCUAUGCCAUCCCCACCCAGCACACCCCCAUCCUCACCUCCAUCCCCAGCCGCAUCCUAGUCCCACCCACCCCCAUCCUCAGUUCCUCCCCCUGCCGUGUGCACCUCCAACACGACGCCUCCGCCCGCUGCCUCCUCCCCCCAGGCCGCCAGGGGAGCCAGGGCUGAGCCACUCGGGGUCGGAGCAACCAGAGCAGACCGGCCUUCUCAUGGGAGGUGCCUCCGGAGGAGCCAGGGGUGGCAGCGGGGGCUUCGGAGACGAGUGCUGAGCCAAGAACCUCCUAGAGGCUGUCCCUGGACCUGGAGCUGCAGGCAUCAGAGAACCAGCCCUGCUCACGCCAUGCCCGCCCCCGCCUUCCCUCUUCCCUCUUCCCUCUCCCUGCCCAGCCCUCCCUUCCUUCCUCUGCCGGCAAGGCAGGGACCCACAGUGGCUGCCUGCCUCCGGGAGGGAAGGAGAGGGAGGGUGGGUGGGUGGGAGGGGGCCUUCCUCCAGGGAAUGUGACUCUCCCAGGCCCCAGAAUAGCUCCUGGACCCAAGCCCAAGGCCCAGCCUGGGACAAGGCUCCGAGGGUCGGCUGGCCGGAGCUAUUUUUACCUCCCGCCUCCCCUGCUGGUCCCCCCACCUGACGUCUUGCUGCAGAGUCUGACACUGGAUUCCCCCCCCUCACCCCGCCCCUGGUCCCACUCCUGCCCCCGCCCUACCUCCGCCCCACCCCAUCAUCUGUGGACACUGGAGUCUGGAAUAAAUGCUGUUUGUCACAUCAACACCA